GGCCUUUUCAAAGGCUGGGUUUCAUUUUAACAAAAUUGGAAAGCCGUGCAUAUUUGGAAUGGCCAGAUCAUCCUGCACCUAAAUGACUUCACCUGUCCAGCUGGGUACAGAAACGGGCUUCUGUCUUUUGUCCCAUUCUUUCAUCUGGCAGUCUCUUCUGAGAAACCUUGACUUUGUUGUCAGAAAAACACUGAUUAGCAUGAGAUCAGAUAGCAGCUGUGAAGAAUGAAAGCGUCACUACCAAUCUCCGGCAGCGUCUGAUAAGGAGAAAUGCACCUCCCUGCGUGCUGCCAAGGUUUAUGGAGCAGAAUUCCCUGACGCCACUGCCCUCACUGCCUGUGCGUGCAUCUGCUGUGGGGUCAUUUCCUUAUUGGACUUGGCUGGGGACCUCCUGAGGGGUGGAUGGGUCAGGACUGGGUAAUUUGGGGAAGGUAUUCGUGGUGUUCCUGUUUGCAGUCUGUGUCCCAGUUGGAAGAGAUGCUUUUAGUGCAUCCAUUAAUCCAGACAUGAUUAGCAAGGGUGUCUCUCCCAGGUAAGAGUUGGUGCGUCUCUUCUGAGUGUCUUUCUCAAGUCUGUUACAAAGAGAACUUUGGUUUCUCAAGGUUUAAGAAUUAAUGUCAAAGAGCAAUUUAGUGUUCGAGUCACCAGCCUUGCUGUGGAUGAUUGCUGAGUCCUCGGAGGUUAGGGCCACAGCACAAUUGGUGGGCCGUCUGUUCCCCACCCUGGUGGAGACUUUCUCACCCAAAGAAAUGUAUUCUGUUAGUAUGUCUCAAUUAGAAUAUUUUAGUAGGAGACAGUUAUGGCUCUUGUUUUAAUUUGUAGUGGAUGAUUACUGUAGCAGGAUCAAGGUUGAGACUUGCAGCGUAGCUCAUGUAAAGCAUUGAUUUUAAACACCCAAAAUAUAUUGCCAGCUUCGUUGCCGUGGCUCCAAGGGACUAGGAAUGCAUAUGUUGUUUUUUGUUAUUAUUUUUUAUUUUUAUUUUUGAAACAAGAGUCUCGCUCUGUCACCCCGGCUGGAGUGCAGUGGUGUGAUCUCAGCUCACUGCAACCUCCACUUCCAGGGUUCAAGCAGUUCUUGUGUCUCAGCCUCCCGAGUAGCUGGGAUUACAGGCACCCGCCACCAUGCCCAGCUAAUUUUGUAUUUUUAGUAGAGACGGGGUCUCACUGUGUUGGCCAGGCUGGUCUCAAACUCCUGACCUCAAGUGAUCUGCCCACCUUGGCCUCCCAAAGUGCUGGCAUUAUAGGCAUGAGCCACUGUGCCUGGCUGCCAUGACCAUUUUAAAUGUGGCAUUGAAUAUCUGCUUUUUUUUUUUUUAAGGCAGUACAGACGUCACCCCUCACACCUCUGUUCUGGGGCUGGUCUGGGCUGGCCAGGAGGGCUUCCAGGCUCGAGGCCGCGUCUGAAGUGUUGUUGGACAAUGUGGAGCUGUGACCCCUUGGUCUUUGGGGACGUGGGGCACCUUGAGAUGCCCACAGUCUUGCGAGGGUUUAUGGCUCAGUGUGUGGCUGCUGCGAGGUAGCUGUGGGCGGGGAGGAAGGAGAGCAGGGUCCAUCUGUCCUGGUGUGGAAAAUGCCCAAGAAAGUCAAGAAAUGGUACAAAAAAUCAUCAUCUGCCCUGGUGCCAUUUCUGUUUAAAAAAAAAAAAAUCACUCUGCGUGCGGUUCUGUGCUUGAGGAGGAUAGAAAAUACCUAGAAAGACGCACAAAGUGUUCUCAUGGGGUCAGCACCGGGAAGUGGGAUGGGAGGCUUGGGAGUGUGUGGAAAGGAGGACAUGGUGUUAUUUUGUUCUGUUUUAUUUGGUAGAGCAAGUGAUCAAAGUGAAGCUUGAGUGAUUGGCGCAGCUUGGCCUGGCCAUGGGUAGAUCCCAGCAUGUCCCGCCUCCCACUGCAGCUCCGUUUCUCGGUCACGGAUGAGACAGGUGGCCUGAGGCUGUGGGCGGAGGAGGGGCAGCCCGGUGUCCCCAGCAGGUGAUUGUCCAGGCUAUUCUUGGGCCAGCCUGAGGGAAGGGGUGGAGGAGAGCUGGGAGGGUGCACAGUGCGCCCCCCCGCCACCCCACCCCGGGACUGGAACUCAGUUCUCAGCCUCGGGCUGGGAGGUGAGCCCAGGCUGCUGUCGAUGGAGGAAGAUGCCGAGGAAGAUGCCCUCAGGAUGGAGGAAGAUGCCAGUGGAGUUUGGUCAGCAGCCAGCGUGGUCUUUCCCGCAGGGGAUACGCAGUGCGCCCACUUGCAGGAAAAACGCUGCUUUAGUUUUUGAAUUUUGCUCAUUCUGUUUAUCGUGCUGCUCAUGCUAAGAUUUGGAUAUCGUUGGUAGGAAUCAGUGUCAAUUGCAUACAGUUGACUCUUGUACCACACAAGCUUGAGCUUUGUGGGUCAACUUAUAUGUGAAUUUUUUCAACCAAACUCAGGGAGAAAAUACAGUGUUCCUGCCAUGUGAAACGUGUGUCGGAGGGCCGACUCUGUACACGCAGGUUCGGCAGGUCCACUUGUGGGGCGUGAGUGUGCCUGGAUUUGGUGUCCAUGGGGUCCUGGAACCGACUCCCUGAGUACAGCGAGGCCGUUUGCAGUAGCAGGUGGUUUCUUUUGUAGUUUCCCCAUUGGUUUCGCCCCACACCAUCUCUCUCAUGCCGCAGCUGCUGCUGAUGAUGACUGAUGACCUGGGUGGGCGAUGCCAGGCCCCCUCUCAGCUCAGGCCACUUCCUUGGAGAGACUCCUGUGCUAAGGGCACCAUUUAGCAAAAGUCCAGAUUUUGGGAUACGGAAAAUUUGGGGGACGUGAAUUCACUCAAAUAAAUGUUCAAAGUUGGCCUCAGAGCCUUGCGUUCUUGUUUUAUAAAAGAUGCACCUUUUGGGGGAAAUACUGCUUAACAACAUUUAACUGGAAAGGCACUGAAACAAAGUUAAGCUUUUUUUGCAUAAUACCUUCACGUGGAUACGGAUUUUCAUAUAAUUGUAAUUGUUACUCAUACAUUCUACUAAGUCUUCUGCUAUUUUUACUUAACGACUUAACAUACUUGUUCAUUCAGUCACGAGUUUGGUUGUUCCACAGUUUGCUGGGGCCUCCCUGGGACCUGAGCACAGUGCUGGGGAUGCAAAAGUAGGUGGUUCCUGAUGGGAUCGUGUCCACGUUGGUGGCUCUGCUUGUAAGGAGUCCACGUUGGUGGGGGAGGCCGACUGGUGACCGGAACCCACGCUGUGACGCCAUCAUUGGUGUGAUGCAGGUGAGGACAGGGUCUGUAGAUAUGCGUGGAGGACGGUGGUCCCAGACCUGGGCAGGUGGAGGUGCCCCUGAGGCCCCCAGUGGACAUUGACUGAGUGUGGCGAGAGCUGGCCAGGAGAGAGUUUGGGAGGUGUGGGAGAGACAAGAGCAGGAGGGGUGGCAGGGGCUAGGAUGGAAAGGGGCUUCUGCAGAAACGGGGGCUGGGGCCUGAGCCCUGGCACCGGGAGAGAUGGAGAGAGGGCAGUGCCGGCUUUGGAAGAGAAACAGCCAGAGCUGUGUAGCCUCGGGGUCCUGCAUGGACACACCCUCAGCUUCCCCCGUGAGGCCCACGAAUCCCAGGGGGAGUUUGUGUUAUGCCACGGACCUCUCACAAGUGGGGGCUGAGGCAGAACUGAGGACAUCUGGGUUCCAUGGUGGAUCAGCCAGGAUUCUGGUUGCAAAUUACAGAAAACAACUUAAACUUAUGCAGGGAAGUGAGCAUGAGGGGGGGUCGGCCCAGAGCACUCUGGCCAGAAGCCAUCUGGGCUCUAAGGCUGGGAGGCCCCUUGCCAGCUCACGUGCUGUGGAAUGGCUUCCCCGCCUCCGGCCCUCGGCAGGUGGAAGGUGCUGCCUGGCAGCCCCUGCAAACUGAAGGGGCCCACGUCCCUCCUGGCUCUGCAUCCCAUUCUCAGGGACACGGCUGUCAUGGGGGGACCAGCUGGGGCAGGGGAAGAGUAUAGGGAACCCAGUAGAAGUGGCCGUGGACUCUCUUAGGAACGAUAACCGGGUCACCUACCAUAGAUGAAGAUGUUGUCGGCCUGCGUUCUUCUCGUGUUGGUCUGGGGCGUGUGGCUGCCGUGGGCUGGCGUUAUCCACAGCCCCGGUCUGGGGCUUGCAGUGGCUGUGGGCUGGCGUGGUCCACAGCCCCGGGCACCAUGGUCCCUGGCCCUGAAAUCGCAUCCAGUGCUGUGUCACCUCGGGCCAGCUGUCUCCUGAGGGGAAGGGAACAGGGAACAGCCCUCCCCGUGUGGCCUCCCCAGCACCACCCACCCCGCAGGACCUCCAGUGUUGACUCUGCUGGGGUCUUCUCUCUCCUGGGGGGUCCUUGUCCCAACGGGAGGACUCCAUGGGCCGCAGGAGGUGUCAAGCUAUUUUCUCUCCUGGAACUGGGUUGCUGGCAGCUCCCAGAUGCAGGAGGAAAGGCUCAGAAUUGCCUUCCUAAUAAGGAAUUGUUGAUGUGAACUUUGGACGGCAAACACUGCUUACAUUUCCUUUUCCGUUUUGAUGUGUUAAUGGUGUGCGGCAACGCCGUGACGCACGGGGACGCAGGUGACGGGCACCCCCCCACAAGGGGACCAUGCACCUGUUUGAUAAUAAGGCAUGCUUCUCUUACUGCAAAUAAAAACUUCAAUGGUUUUCUGCCAGAAAGACCCUGUCUUUUAUGUAGGAUACAUAGAGGAUCAUUUGGCAAGUGAUUGGGGAUUUUGGGUUAAACUAAAAAUAAAUUAAUUUCAUUUUAUAGCACUCUGAACACAUUUGAGUUAAUUAUUCAUCGAGAAUUUGAAUAGCACACACUGUUCUGACUUCCGACUUCCCCCAAUGAAUGGCAUUUGCUGUAACGUGACAAAACCCUGAGUCUUAGAAUUAUUGGGUAAUGUGAAAAAAGGAAAAGUUGGUUCUCUGUUGUUUUGCUUUAAGGAAAUUAUAUUAUUUUACAGUCACUUAGUUUUCUCCUUUCCAAUAAGAAAAAUUGCUUUCUUACUACCUGAAAAUUCGUGAAGGUCAAGGGGACACACCCUGCAGUGCAUUAAAAGCCACCAUCAAAUGUGGACCUGGACUCAGUUUCCCUCUGUUCCCUCCCACCCUCAAAUGUGGACGUGGACUCAGUUUCCCUGUUCUCUCCCACCAUCCAAUGUGGACGUGGACUCAGUUUCCCUCUGUUCUCUCCCACCCUCAAAUGUUGACGUGGACUCAGUUUUCCUCUGUUCUCGCCCACCAUCAAAUGUGGACGUGGACUCAGUUUCCCUCUGUUCUCUCCCACCGUCAAAUGUGGACGUGGACUCAGUUUCCCUCUGUUCUCGCCCACCGUCCACUGUGGACGUGGACUAAGUUUCGCUCUGUUCUCUCCCACCGUCCAAUGUGGACGUGGACUCAGUUUCCCUAUGUUCUCUCCCACCAUCCAAUGUGGACGUGGACUCAGUUUCCCUCUGUUCUCACCCACCCUCAAAUGUGGAUGUGGGCUCAGUUUCCCUCUGUUGUCUCCCACCAUCAAAUGUGGACGUGGACUCAGUUUGCCUCUGUUCUCUCCCACCAUCCAAUGUGGACGUGGACUCAGUUUCCCUCUGUUCUCUCCCACCCUCAAAUGUUGACGUGGACUCAGUUUUCCUCUGUUCUCGCCCACCGUCAAAUGUGGACGUGGACUCAGUUUCCCUCUGUUCUCUCCCACCGUCAAAUGUGGACGUGGACUCAGUUUCCCUCUGUUCUCGCCCACUGUCCACUGUGGACGUGGACUCAGUUUCGCUCUGUUCUCUCCUACCGUCCAAUGUGGACGUGGACUCAGUUUCCCUAUGUUCUCUCCCACCAUCCAAUGUGGACGUGGACUCAGUUUCCCUCUGUUCUCACCCACCCUCAAAUGUGGACGUGGACUCAGUUUCCCUCUGUUCUUGCCCACCCUCAAAUGUGGACGUGGACUCAGUUUCCCUCUGUUCUCGCCCACCAUCCAAUGUGGAUGUGGGCUCAGUUUCCCUCUGUUCUCUCCCACCAUCAAAUGUGGACGUGGACUCAGUUUGCCUCUGUUCUCUCCCACUGUGAAAUGUGGACGUGGACUCAGUUUCCUUCUGGUCUCGCCCACCAUCCAGUGUGGACGUGGACUCAGUUUUGCUCUGUUCUCUCCCACCAUCCAAUGUGGACGUGGACUCAGUUUUGCUCUGUUCUCUCCCACCAUCCAAUGUGGAUGUGGACUCAGUUUCCCUUUGUUCUCGCCCACCGUCCAAUGUGGACUUGGACUGUUUCCCUCUGUUCUCGCCCACUGUCCAAUGUGGACGUGGACUCAGUUUCCCUCUGUUCUUGCCCACUGUCCAAUGUGGACGUGGACUCAGUUUCCUUCUGUUCUCGCCCACCGUCCAAUGUGGACGUGGACUGUUUCCAUCUGUUCUCGCCCACCGUCCAAUGUGGACGUGGACUCAGUUUCCCUCUGUUCUCUCCCACCGUCAAAUGUGGACGUGGACUCAGUUUCCCUCUGUUCUCUCCCACCGUCCAAUGUGGAUGUGGACUCAGUUUCCCUCUGUUCUCUCCCGCCAUCAAAUGUGGACGUGGAUUCAGUUUCCCUCUGUUCUCUCCCACCAUCCAAUGUCGACGUGGACUCAGUUUCCCUCUGUUCUCUCCCACCGUCAAAUGUGGACGUGGACUCAGUUUCCCUCUGUUCUCUCCCACCAUCCAAUGUGGACGUGGACUCAGUUUUGCUCUGUUCUCUCCCACCAUCCAAUGUGGACGUGGACUCAGUUUCCCUCUGUUCUCUCCCACCAUCCAGUGUGGACGUGGGCUCAGUUUCCCUCUGUUCUCUCCCACCAUCCAAUGUGGACGUGGAUUCAGUUUCCCUCUGUUCUCUCCCACCAUCCAAUGUCGACGUGGACUCAGUUUCCCUCUGUUCUCUCCCACCGUCAAAUGUGGACGUGGACUCAGUUUCCCUCUGUUCUCUCCCACCAUCCAAUGUGGACGUGGACUCAGUUUCCCUGUUCUCGCCCACCGUCCAAUGUGGACGUGGACUCAGUUUCCUUCUGUUCUCGCCCACCAUCCAAUGUGGAUGUGGACUCAAUUUCGCUCUGUUCUCUCCCACCAUCCAAUGUGGACGUGGACUCAGUUUCCCUCUGUUCUCUCCCGCCGUCCAAUGUGGACGUGGACUCAGUUUCCCUCUGUUCUCUCCCGCCGUCCAAUGUGGACGUGGACUCAGUUUCCCUCUGUUCUCUCCCACCGUCCAAUGUGGACGUGGACUCAGUUUCCCUCUGUUCUCUCCCACUGUGAAAUGUGGACGUGGACUCAGUUUCCCUCUGUUCUCUCCCACCGUCCAAUGUGGAUGUGGACUCAGUUUUCCUCUGUUCUCUCCCACCGUCAAAUGUGGACGUGGACUCAGUUUCCCUCUGUUCUCUCCCACCGUCAAAUGUGGACGUGGACUCAGUUUCCCUCUGUUCUCUCCUACUGUCAAAUGUGGACAUGGACUCAGUUUCCCUCUGUUCUCGCCCAGCUUGCCACCAUGGCUCAUUUCACUUUCACUCAGGAAAGGAAGAAACAUUGUUUUUAAUAGGUAUGAAGGCAGUUGUUUUUAACCUAAGGAACAGAACAUAAUUCUAGCAAUGGAAAUUACCAACCGAGUCUGUGUGAGGUUUGGAAGAAAAAAAGGAUUUUCACUUCCACACUCUGUGUGUGCCCACCUCCCCCAGUUGAGAGUCACAGAUUUAAUUACUUUAAUUUUGAGCUUAAAAUAAUUUGACAGCCUAACAAAAACUACUACAGUCCUAUAAAAUUCUGCUUGUGUGUUUGGUUUUUCAGUUGCUUGGCUUAAUAUGGUGAAUGAAUGCAUUAUGAGUUGUUAUUUUAGUAAUUGCUAUAAAAAUUAAUGUACGUUAUAGCCAAGUGUUAUAAAAUUAAUUUAACAGCAAAGUAAAACUAAAGCUGCAUUGAUUUCUCACUGUACUUGUGCUUAAAGACGGCUCCAUGAGGCAGGCCCUGUGAUCCUGCAGGCCGGCAGGAGCAGGUGCUACCUGGCUGGUGCGGUCGCCACCCGUCCCCUCUUGCUGCCAGGCAGCUUUGCAGUUUCCAGGCUAUGGGGGAGUCGAGGCGGGUGGUCAGUAAGAGACAGUGGGGAGUUGGGUGGUGCAGGUUGGCGUGGGGUGGAAGGAGGCGUGGAGUGUGGGUGUGGAGAGCCUGGGGGAGGCUGGACAGCAGCUCCAGUACCUGCACAGGGGGACAGGGUGCGGGGGGCACGGGGCAGUGAGUCGCUCCUGGAAACAGCCCUUGGGGUUUUUAUAGAUGGGCCUGUCGUCAGCUCUGCACCACAUUCCUGCUGGGGCUGGGUGGAGAGUGGAGGCCUCGAGCAUGCGUUUCUCCAGGUGAGGGCCCAGCUGACACAGCCAGUGUUUCCUGGAGGCCCCUCACCUGGGAACGUGCCCCUGCUCUUCUCAGAACAAAAUAAAUCUUAAACUCUACACAUCACCUUUCCAGAAAGUGUUUAAGUCUGUGUGCCUGUUAACUCACCUAAAUUUAAAGAGUAAUGAUACAAUAUGCUUCUUUUUAGGGGAGAAAACUUAGCUGAUUUAAAAGAUAAAAUCAGAGGUCGGGGGACGCAGCAUUUUGGGGGAGACAGGGUUUAUGUCCUAGUGGUCAGCAGUGUUUCCUGAACUAUUGUGUUUGCUCUAUUAUUACAUUACAGAAGUGACACGUCAAACCUAGGGAAAUAGGCAAAAUAGCCCCCCCCAUUCAGAGAUAAACGUUAUCAACAUAUUCAUGCACUUCCUUCUGUUUUUGCUGUUUGCUUUUUAAGACCACGUUCAUAGGAUGGGUAUAUAAUUGUUUACAGUGACUUUAAAAGCACCUUUCUUGUUAAAAAGAGUAUUUUUUCAUUCUGGAAAAUUUAGACAACAUGUUUUGUUUAAAAAUUACUUAUAAUACCACCAUCAAGUCAUCAAUGUUUUUAUACAUUCUCUUGGUCUCUUUAUGGACUUAAUAUAUACAAUUUAACAGAUGGGAAAUAACAUAAUUUUAUGAGUAAAAUGUUUCUUGGCGUUAGAGAUGGAGCAGAGAGGAGGCACAGGGCUUCCUGCUGGCUGAGGUGUGUGGCCAGGGUGUGACCAGUGGCCUCCCAAGUUUAGGGUCUGCAUGGAGAAGGAUUUCUAAAUCACCUUACACCACACCCCCUGCAGCCGUGUGCCACUUUGAUAAGGGGGUGUACUCUGAUAGACUUUUCAAGACAAGACUCUGCUGGAUCUGAGGCUGUUUUGGCUGCUUCUGGAGACUCAGCUCUGGAACGUUCAUGCCAGCUCUCCCUCAAGACCCCACGGAUGCCAUGUCCUCAUCUUUUGGAAUCCAGUGUUGUAGAGGAGAAGUCUGAGGCCAGUUUGAUUUUUGCUUCAUGGUAGGAAACUGAUGUUUUCAGGCUUUUCCCCUUUAUUUCCAUGAUGAAGAUGAUGUCCCACCUCAUCCGGAGGGGUCUUUCUUGUCUUGUCGGGAACAUCCAGCUUUUAGGUGCCUCUUCAGGUCCUCAGUCCCUUUCUCACCUUCCUCACAGUCCUCCCCAUCUCAUCCAUCUUCACUGUAAUUCGGUUAUUUUUUCAUUUUUAUGCUCACUUUCCCAUGCGACUUUUGUUCUUGUUUCACAGAUGCUGGUGCUAAAUUGUAUGUCUGAGGCCCAGGGGCCGUGUUUCAUUCUGUCUGCCUCUGCAUGUACUUUUGAGAAGUAGGGGCAGGGUUGCCCCCUAGAUGCUGUUUCAGCUGGACCUGCCCAGGCUCCCUGAAGUGGGGGCAUUGGGCAGAGCCCAUGUGGCUCUAUGGUGGGCCGUGUUGCUGAACCCUACGUCUGAGAUUUGGGGGCCGUGUUUCAUUCUGUCUGCCUCUGUGUGUACUUUUGAGAAGUGGGGGUGGGGGUUGCCCCCGGACGUUGUUUCAGCUGCACCUGCCCAGACUCCCUGAAGUGGGGGCGUCAGGCAGAACCCGUGUGGCUCUACGGCGGGCCGUGUUGCUGACAGAGCAAGAAGCCGCGCUCCCAGGACGCGCCUGCAGCUGUGGGCAAGUCUGGGAUUGUGAUGGGAUCGUUUCCUUCUCUAAAAUACGUCUCAACUAUUAUCCAGAGGGUUGGCUGUAGGCUUUCAACAGCUUCACUCUUCUUAGUGACCAGGAGACAAUUCACUAAACAGAGUUGCUGUCAGGGUUUAAUUAGUCAGGAGUUUCUGCCAGAGGCUGGCGGGACAGCUCCCUCUGCAAGCCUCCUGCAGCCUCCCCAUCCCCACUCUUGGGCCCGGCCACCUGCCUUGGUCUGCAGAAGGUGCACAUUCUCUGUUCUCCUGAGGGGCUCCUGGACUUCAGGACAGCCUUGGCAAGCUGAUGUGUAACUCCCAGUCUCUUCUCUUUUUUAGUAAGGAAUACGCUCACGGAAUCCUGACCUUCUAGAUUGUUUCAUCUUUUUAAAACAGCCGCAGCUUCCUAAGCCACCUUGUGUCUGAGUGUGAAUCACUUAUUAUUUUUCACUGCAGAAUGAACAGAACUGGAAUCAUAGGAUUUAGAGGGUGAUAAAAAGACAGAGGUUAGGAUAUUCUAUUUUCUCACCUCUUCCAUACACUUUUUCCUUAAAUACACCCUCAUACGUCUGUGAAGUUCUUCCCAAUUCUGUAACUUCACUCCACCCUCAGGUGGAACAUUUGUGAACAGUAACAAGUAUUGAUGUGUGCAACUCUGCAACCCAGCUGGAAUUAAUGCUUUUUAUUUAUCAAUGGAUGGUCAUUGGAUGGCCAGAGGGAUUCCCUGUGCAUUGUGGGGGCCCAGUGCCUGCUUGUGAGUGACAUGGACAUAACGAGGGUUAGGGAAUCUCAGCCUCUGUGAUUCGAGUAGUGACAUCAAGGCAGGUGGAUGACUCUUUGAGCUUGGCAUGCUCCUGGGUGGCACAGCACAGGUGACGUGGACUGGGGCAAGGGCUUGUUCCACGGGCUUCUGUGUUGUUUUUUGUUUUUGUUUUUUUUUGAGAUGGAGUCUCACUCUGUCACCCAGGCUGGAGUGCAGUGGUGCGAUCUCAGUUCACUGCAGGCUCCGCCUCCCGGGUUCGUGCCAUUCUCCUGCCUCAGCCUCCCCAGUAGCUGGGACUAUAGGUACCCGCCACCACGCCUGGCUAAUUUUUUUGUAUUUUUAGUAGAGACGGGGUUUUACCGUGUUAGCCAGGAUGGUCUCGAUCUCUGACAUCAUGAUCCACCCGCCUUGGCCUCCCAAAGUGCUGGGAUUACAGGCCUGAGCCACCGUGCCCGGCCUGUUUUUUUUUUUUUGAGACGGAGUCUCACUCUGUUGCCCAGGCUGGAGUGCAGUGGCGCGAUCUUGGGUCACUGCAACCUCCACUCACUGCAAUCUCUGCCUCCCGGUUCAAGCCGUUGUCCUGCCUCAGCCCCCAAGUAGCUGGGAUUACAGACAUGUGCCACCAUGCCUGGCUGAUUUUUGUAUUUUUAGUAGAGACGGGAUUUUGCCAUGUUGGUCUGGCUGGUCUUAAACUGUUGGCCUCAAGUGAUCUGCCCACCUUGGCCUCCCAAAGUGCUGAGAUUACAGGUGUGGGCCACCGUGCCCGGCCCUGUGUUUGAUUCUUAAAUCUUCUUUUUCUUUUUAAUCUUUCUCUUUCUGGAGGACCACUCAGUGGAUAUGAGGAAGAGUUCACAGAUGUCCAUAUUACAUUCCUUUCUUAAAUUAGCCUCCCUUGAACACUGCUGUAGGGUACAGACGCAUGAAGGGCUGAAAGGGUGGUUGUGUCCCAGUAAGUGUGAGAGUGGAGCUGGUCUGUGAGACCCCGGUGCCGGUGAGGGCACCCGUGUGCGAUGGCCUGGGACGGGGGUGUGCGGAGCCCUGACCGUGGCACACGCCCUUCAGCUUUGAUGUUUCAGGCCCUUGCUCUGGUCAUCAGUGAGCAGAAGGUCUAACAGCAGUGAUAUUUAUCACUAGUUGUGUUGGCCAAUGUGUUAGGAGGGUGAAGCUGUUUGACUUAAGCUGCUUGAUUGGUUUGCAUUUAAAUAGACACCUGGUGGCCUGGUGCCUGGACACUUGCUCUGUGACCUGCCCCGUGUGGCUCCUCCCUCUGGCAUGCAUUAGAUGAGAUGGGCGUGUUUAGGGCGAUGUGGCCCUAGACUGGAAUGCAUUCGAAGUGCAAACCCUGCCCCACCCCAGACCUGCCCCACCCCAGUGUGACGUUAGGAGGCGGAGGCCCAGCAUCCUUCACCUGCCCUCCAGGUGGGUCUGAGGAUGCUGAGGUUUCAGAGCACUGCUUUGCUAGCACACCAGCGAGUCCUGCUUAAAGAGGCCAGGAUCUGAAAGGGCAGGUUACCAAAUUGUGUAGCAGAAAAAUAGAAAUGUUUCCUUAGAAGGGGUGUAGGAAGGAAAAUAAUUUCCUUCAUCAUAUCUGGAAAAGAUUUCAAAUUAGUAGGCACUAUUUGGAAUUAUUAGUGGUCUCCUGUAUUUCUUUCUUUCUUUCCUUUUUUUGAUACAGGGUCUCGCCCUGUUGCCCAGGCUGGAGUGCAGUGGUGCAAUCUUGGCUCCCUGCAACCUCUGCCUCCUGGGCUCAGGUGAUCCUCCCACCUCAGCCCCCUGAGUAGCUGGGACUACAGGCGCGCUACCACACCUGGCUCAUUUUUGUAUUUUUUUUUGUAGAGAUGGGGUCUUGCUAUGUUGCCCAGGCUGGUCUCGAAUUCCAGCAUUUCUUCUGCCUCAGCCCCCCAAAAUGCUUCUGUACCCCUGCCCCAACAAGGAAGGACAAGAGGUGUGAGCCACACACACGCCUGGCCUCCUGUCUUUCCUUGUUGGAGCAGGGAUGUAGAAGCACUUGCCGCAGCCGACUUGAGUACAUCUGACUUUACUUAGCUUUCCUCAUGGGUAGCCUGGCAGUGCUGUGCACCAGUGCUGCUGGCCAGCUGUUUUUUCAAUGUACUGGCAGAAAAUCAAGCUGACACCCGGGUUCCUUUCUCCCUGGGUACUGACCAGGUGGGAGAGGAGGGGCGUUGUGUGAGUAUCAUCUUCAUGAGGGCUGGUGGGGGAACAUCAGCUUUAAGGUGCCUGGGAUCUAAGGCAUGGAACCCAGCAGUGCAGAGGAACGUAGGGGAUGUAGCCUCGGGAGCAGAGAUGUGCGGGCCGGUGCCCUCGUUCCUGGCGGGGUCUGAGUGCAGGAAUAGGUUGGUGACCCAGCCGAGGUCACAAGACCUGCCUGGAUGCAUGGCUGGCGUCCGUGCUGGCCCCAAAACUGCCCAUUUGGGGAUUCCCCUCAGUCACAGACUCACCUAGGGGUCCGGAGAGCGUCCCCACUAUGACCUCAAAGAACGAGGUGUUGCCUUGAGAUCUUCCAAGGUGAGGGUAGGAUUUUUUUUUUUUUGCAAUUAGCAAUAAUUUGUUGUGAAUGAUCUUGGACCUAUUUUCCACUUCUUUGUAUAGGAAGAGAGACAGAAUAAAAAGUCUCAAUGUGCCAGAUGCCAUGUAAUGAAGCCAUGGGGUUAACGUUGUUGAUUAUUACGUAGCAUCACGUUAAUUGGAACAUAUUCACACGUGUCCACAGCGUGUGCGUGUGCCCAGUCCGAUGAGCACGUUGGGUUAGGGUCGCUGCUGGUUCAUGCAGCCCCUCUGGGUGGGGCUGUCUCUGUGGCUUGGCCAACACCCUUGCUGCUGCCACUGUUGGAGUCUCCAGCCUUGACCGGCCUUGCUGCCCCCAGGUUCUCGGAGCCUGCGCACCCUCUUCCCGGCGCCCACCCUCUUCCCGGCGCCCACCCUCUUCCCGGCGCCCACCCUCUUCCCCGCGCGCAGCCUCUUCCCCGCGCGCAGCCUCUUCCCCGCGCGCACCCUCAUCCCCGCGCGCACCCUCUUCCCCGCGCGCACCCUCAUCCCCGCGCGCAGCUUCUUCCCCGCGCGCACCCUCGUCCCGGCACGCACCCUCGUCCCCCGUCGCGUCUACCCGGGGUCUGUCGUGUGUUUCUACUCUGGCCAUGCCCGCCUCUUGCUGUGAGCUAAGUUUAUUGAGGUGCAGUAAGAAACCAACAGAGGGGAGCAGAGUCCGAGGCUGUCAGGGCGCAAGGGAGCCUUGGGCAUCUCUUCCCCAGCUCUGGCGACCCACCCUUCGGGUUGAAGUGCAGGGGAGAGGUGAGUUCUAAAGGUAAGGCUGCGGUGAUUUCCUGAGCCUUAAUUAUCUAACACUUGGCCAUCUGCCGUGUGACCCCAUCGAAGGGCACCUCUGGGGACAAAGCAAAGCCCUUGGUGGCCGUGGGCGGGGCGGCCGUGCCUGUCUGUGUGUCCUGCACCGGGAGCCCCGCCAGCCGUGGGGACGUUCAGGCACUUGCCACCUGUGGGAGGUGUGUGUUAGCCGCGUGGUAGGUGCGGAUGCGUGGAGGGACAGGCACAGGCCCACAGGCGUGGCGGGUAUGGGAGAUUUAGCCGCGUGGAGAUGCGUGGAGGGACAUGCACAGGCCCACAUGCGUGGCGGGUGUGGGAGAUUUAGCCGCGUGGGGAUGCGUGGAGGGACAUGCACAGGCCCACAGGCGUGGCGGGUGUGGGAGAAAGCGCGCAGAGUGCCCAGCAGAUGCCGCGUGGUCAGCGGAAGCCUUGGAUACAGGCCGGGCGGGGGAGGGACAUCUGGAAAUACGCUUUAAGCAGCAUCAAUGGAUAAUGCUGUGAUUUUCCUUCUUUUCGUGGUCCAAAACACGUUCUAGUGAUGUCGCUGAUUUGUGUGUACCUGGGACAAGGAACUAAAUAUAUUAGGGCCUUGAUGUAAUCUGUAAAACAGGCACAAUAUGCCUAUUUCAAAGAGGCAGUGGACAUGAAAGACUGCUCUAAACUAUUCAGUGCAAUGAGAAUGCUUCGUUGUCAUUAGCAAAGUAAAAUGCCUCCAAGGCGAGCUUGCCAUGCGUUUAAUGACCUUGGACGUGAGCUUCCUAAACCUGCCAGAAAGUGCUUCCAGCGUGGCUUCAUGCAGUGGCUUCAGUGGAGAAUGUGCAUAUGCGGCUGAUACUGAGAGCCGGGCAGCACCCUGACAGCCUGACACAUCCCCAUGUGUGGACCGUGAGCCGGGCAGCACCCUCCCAACCUGACGCGUCCCCAUGUGUGGACCGUGAGCCGGACAGCACUCUCCCGACCUGACACAUCCCCAUGUGUGGACCGUGAGCCGGGCAGCACCCUCCCGACCUGACACAUCCCCACGUGUGGACCGUGAGCCGGGCAGCACCCUCCCGACCUGACGCGUCCCCACGUGUGGACCGUGAGCCGGGCAGCACCCCCCGACCUGACGCGUCCCCAUGUGUGGACCGUGAGCCGGGCAGCACCCUGAUGGCCUGACGCGUCCACAUGUGUGGACCGGGAGCCGGGCAGCACCCUCCCGACCUGACGCGUCCCCAUGUGUGGACUGUGAGCCGGGCAGCAUCCUCCCGACCUGACGGGUCCCCUUGUGCCCAUUGUGGGACCUCCAUCAUGCAGGCAGGUGACAUGCAUCAAACUGAAUGCAAGGAGGAGGGUCCAGGAUUGUGUGCGGGCUCCGUGUCUCGUCCUUCUGAGGCCUUCUGGGAAGCCAGGAGGGCAGUGGGGUCUUUUGUGUGUUUCCUCCUGGUGGCCGUGGGUUUGUAGAAAUGGCUUUUUGCAAAAGGGCCCGGAGGCGGAAUUAGAGCCUGUCCUGGAAAGGAUGAUGCCUUCGCGGGCACCUCUUUCCAUUACUCCAGUGCUCCCGUGAUUUUAAAUAUGUGCACCCUGCAGACUUCAGCCUUCUAGUGUCCUGGGUGAAUAAAUGCCAGGAUUGCUCCAAUGCUGGCAAACCUGAAACAGGAAUUUCUCUGCAUUAAGUUUGUCACCAAAAUGGGAGGUAAGGGGAGAGGGGAAGGAACUUCUUGGCCUCGUCAGCCCUUUUCUUGAAACUCACAGUCAAACUUUGUCAAGUUCUAGGUGAUAGUGCUUGAGGCGAUGCACUUAUUUAUGUUAUGUCUUGUUUUCUGAGUACGGUGCUUCGAGAAUUUAAAUAUUUAGGUGAAAUUGCCAUGCACAGUUGAAUUGGCACCAUAAUUUGACUCUCUGUAAAGCCUUUUGGUUUCCUGUUAGAGUGACCAUUUUUUGAGUCAACUGAAGCAAACCCUGCUGUCAGCACGAAGGAGCCACUUUAUAGUUAGGAGAUCAAAUUAAAUAGAAUUCUCCUAAAUAGAGCGUGCUCUUUUCAUAAAUUUUAAAAAUUCAUUUAUUCAUCAAACACAUACUGAGUACUUAUCACCCUGGUUGCUAGUUACUGUUCAUAUAUGUUUUUAAGGAAUUACUUCCACCUAGCUCUGAAAUAACAUUGCAUUUAGAAUUUAGCCCAGAGGUGAUUAAGCAUGAGCUUUUCACAGCAGUCCUGUUUUCAUUUUUACUUGAGAACAUGUUCUCAGACUCGGUGCCCAGCUGACGUUACCUGUGCAUUGCCCGAGGCACACACCUGGCCGGGGCUGUGUCUCGGGGGCUUCAGAAGAGGAAGGAAGGGCUGCCAGGCAUCUGGCCCUUCCACGUUUCCCUGGUGGAGGGAUUAGGCCUUGGGCAGGAGUCUUGGCUUGUCUUAAUGGAUGAGCUUGUGUCUCUCAGUCAGCUCUGCCUUGGUGUUAAGCUCUGGACUGACUCUGACCUCUGAGUGGCAGAGGAGAGGACGGUGAUUUAGAAUCAGUCAUGCAGACCAGGGCACUCAGCGGGUCUUGGGUAAAAAGUGGUGGCAAUCGAUUGCUUGCCCUUUUGGGAGAACUGUGUGGAUUGACUCCUCUGAAGACCUCUUUGUUUUGAUUUUAUCUUGAGACUUUGUAGAAGCAAAAAUGCCUUUAAACAAAAUUAAAUGAUGGGCUUUUGUAAUGUUUGUGUCUCCCCAAGAUUCACAAUUGGAAUCCUCACCCCGGAGGAGAUGGUGCUAGGAGGGGGAGCUUUGGGUGGUGAGGAGGUCAUGAGGGUCUCAUAAAUGGGAUUUGUGCCCUCAUAAAAGGGACUACAGAGAGCUCCCUCGCUCCUUCCACUGUGUGCGGACCCAGUGAGAAGGCGCCGUCUGUGAACCAGGAAGCCCUCACCAGACAAACCUGUCAGGUCUUGACCAUGGACUUCCUAGCCUGAGAGCUGUGAGAAAUGAACUUGUGUUGCUUGUCAGCCCCCGCCCAGCCUAUGGUGUGUUGUUACAGCAGCCUAGGUGGACAAAGGCAGGUUGUGAAUUUUCUGUUGUUUGUCAGUCCCCGCCCAGCCUAUGGUGUGUUGUUACAGCAGCCUAGGUGGACGAAGGCAGGUUGUGAAUUUUCUGUUGCUUGUCAGCCCCCGCCCAGCCUAUGGUGUGUUGUUACAGCAGCCUAGGUGGACAAAGGCAGGUUGUGAAUUUUCUGUCAGAUUUUCUGGCUUCAGAUACCUGGUAGGGAAAUGUCACCAUCUUACGCAGGUGGGACCGUGUGGAAUCAGACGUUAUGUUAUGAUUUGACCCUGUUCUUGCCCCACGCCUGUGCAGUUCACACCUCCAGGUGUCUCGGCUGCCCGCGGCCCCUCCAGGUGUUUCUGAUGCGGGGAUGUGGGUGCUGGUGCACACGAGUCCCAUGUGGUGCCGGUCGCAGCUAUGCCGUCGGGGAGCAGGACUAGGAGCUCCCGCCCCUCGUGAACCAGCAGCCUCACCGGGAAGCUGCUGAGAAGUGUAUGACGGAAGGUGAUUGCGCCUCGAGACUGAAACUUCCUGUUUACAGGGAACUGAGGUGCAUAAGAGGGAAUUUAAUGAUGCCCUGAGAGACAGAUGCAUCUGGGGGACGUUCUGCAGGACGUUGGCCCCAGACUCUCGAAAAGUCAUCACAGAUAAAGGGUGUGAGGCUGUCCCUGACGAAGAUGGGGAAGGAGAGUCACUCGGCGCAGUGUGUGGCCCAGAUAGAAAAGACGUUUUCGGGAGAAUUGUGCUUAUUGAAUAUAAAGUGGACAGCGAUGCUCUGAAAUGGUUCUUGUCUGCCGAUGAUGGUUCUGCGGCUGCAGAGGGUCCUUUAUUCUUAGGGAACGCGUGCGUGAGGACUCGGCGAGGUGGCAGGAGCCUGUCACCUUCAACUGGCUCCAGAGGAGAAACGAAUCUGUCUCUCUGUAUAAUCUACAGAGAGAGAGAGUGAGAAAGCAAAUCUACCGAAAUGUUAGUUGUCGGAACUCCACGUGGAGAAAACUUGGCCACUCAUUGUACUGUUCUUCCACUUUUUAAAUAUGUUUGAACAUUUUCAUAAUGAAAAUGUGGGAAAGUAAAAAUACAUCUGGAAAUUGGUAUGGAAGUGAGUCAAGCCAAGCACCCUUGGGUUCAGCCGGGAAGAGCCGACGAGCCGACGAGCCGUUGGUGUUCUGUCGACUUGUGGGGAUUUCCUCCUCCUGGGUUCACCACCUAGUUUUCCUUGUGAUAAAGUUAUUUUGUAUGUAGCUAUGAGCACAGGUUGAUGCUGGAAACACACAUGUAGUGUGGAUUGUCAUUAAGAAUGUGGAGAACUGGCUAAAGAAACCACUUGUACAGUUUUGAGAUGAGCACUGCCUGCCUCAGCAUCUGUGGUAACGGCUUCACUUGGGUGCAGAGCUUGGCAGAGGUUUGAGUGACUCUAUCUCGAUGAUCGUCUGUCAGAGGACAAGGUUAAGUGUCACCACCGAGGACCCCGUUGAGCCUCUGGGCUGGAAGUAACUUCCCCUGGGCCGGUGAGGCAGCCUCUGGGGGUCUUUCCUGACAAGACCCUUCACUGAGCUGCAGUUUGGCCACCUCUGCCCUCGCCUCCCUGACUGCAGGGCCUCGAGGUCUCACCACCUCCAGCCUGAGCGCCCAGUGCCCAGGGGCAAUUUCCCGCCUUCCCCGGGGGCUCAGGAUGCUGGCUCCUGGGGCAGUGCCCGCAGCUGGGCCCCUCCUCCAGGGCUGGCCACGGCCUCCUGCUGUGUCAUACCAGCUGCUUCCCCGCAGCUGCAGCCCACACUGCGCGGCCGCUUCUGCUUCUGUUGGAUGAGGAGACGCAGGCCCUCGCCCAGGCCCCCAUGGGCCCUCAACGCCCCAGAGACCCGGCUUCCCGGCCUCGCCCCUGCUGGCCCUAAGGCUGUGCCACCUCCCCCUGCCCAGUCCCUGGUCUCUGUACAGUGUCUGUCCAGGACGUCUAUCCAUCCAUCCUUGACAACCUGUCCAGAUGAGGCCACUGUUAUCCCAGUCUGUGAGGGGCGAUCACAGCCCAGGUGCCGGCCGAUGUGGAGACGCUGAUGGACUUCAGUGUGCAGGAAAGUGAGUUCCUUCAUAUCCACAGCCAGCUGGGAGCCCACCCCAUUCACAGGUGGAUUUGCCUUGUUUUUUGGCCCAAUCACCUACAUUAAAUCAGAAGAAUCACAGUUCCCUGCUCUUCUGGUUUUUGUGACUGUCCGCCUCUCUCCUCUGCCUUGGAUUGGAGGGUGGGGUGUGUCAUGGGUUCGUGGAAUCCUCUCUCUGUUCUUGUGUAGCCACCAGGGACUGUUAUCCAGGCUGAUUCCACAGGAGGAGUUUGGGGUGAGUUCCUGAGCGAGAGUUGGGAAGACUGACGUCUGCGUAAAUCUUGCUUGUUCGUGGUUAUUCCUCUCAGUCUUCUUAAAUUCUGAAAAAUUGGGGGCCAAUUAGAAAUAAGGAUUUAGGUAUGGAUCGGUGAGGACAGAAUGUUGAUCUAAUUGGCUUUACGUUGUGUGUGAUAAUUUUACGCUACCCUCCGGAAGAACUUAAGAUGUUGACAGUGUCGUGAGAAUCAUUUUUUUCUUUUUCUUUUUCUUUUUCUUUUUUUUUUAUUUUUGAGAUGGAGUCUCGUUCUUUUUGCCCAGGCUGGAGUGCAAUGGUGCAAUCUUGGCUCACUGCAAUCUCUGCCUCCUGGGUUCAAACAAUUCUCCUGCCUCAGCCCCCCAGUAGCUGAGAUUAUAGGUGCUCACCAACACACCCAGCUAAAUUUUUGUAUUUUUAGUAGAGACAGGGUUUCACUCUUAAGGACGUUGUUCAGUAAGUACUAAUUGGUGGCCUGCCGUUGAACUAAUUUCAGUGUAGUACUGACAUCAUCAGCCACGGCAGAAACUUACUUGGCAUCCCUGGAAGAGAGGGCAGGGAAGCAUAGCAACCUGAAACCACCUCAUUCUCCAGCGCUACUUCCAACUCUGAGCUGAUGGUCAUUACGAGUGGAUCUGCCCUGGACAAGUAGUUUAGUGUAGCUGCCUUGGACGGGCAGGUGAAAAGUAACAAACCGCCAGAAAACUCAGCUAAUAAAAUGUUAGGAGAGACUUGGGGCACCAGGAAGGGGUGAGGCCUGUCUGUGUGCCAUCUGUGUGGAGCCUCAGUAUCUAGGGGACAGCGUUGACGCUGAGCCCCAGGUUUUUAUUAGUGUUUCCCUGAAUAAAACGCCACUCCUGAGCUGUGGACUGGGAGGCUCUUUCUGAUGAUUAGGCUUCAUAAUGCGGGAUCACUAGGCAAGGUGGAUGUGAGGGCCAUAGGAUCUGGAGACUGUCCAGGACUGCUUUCUGGAAGGCGGCCAGCCUGCUGGAGGGGGACAACAGGCUUGUCCCUUCAGCAGUGAAGCCACCAAAGAGAGUCUUUUUGAGAAUAAAAGAGAGAAGCUUUUAAGGAAAAAAAGCAGUUUCUGUCUCUGUUUGGGAGUUGAGUGCAUUUUCCUGCAUUUAUUCAGAGAUGUUCGUCAGUUCCCACUGUGUGCCGGGGCCCCGCUAUGGGGUAGGGUCACCCCACCGCGUACCUAACCCAGGAAAACUCGUCUGCAGUUAUUUCAGAGGCUGUUUGCAUUUCUUGUGCUUCAAUGGGUGGAGGGAGUUUUUCCUCCUACUGUUUUUAGUCAGUUUUCUUAAUCUAGCCUGUUACUGGGAUAAGUUCCAGAGCCGAGCAGUUUUAAAAACAAUCUUUGCACCUUGCAUGGAGAGCAGUCCAUCUGUGGGUGGUUUGUUCCUGGAGGUGCUGCAGUGGCCUUGGGUGACGCGAGGGCCCCCUGGCUCAGGAUGGGCCGAGAGAGGAAUGCGUGAGCAGUGGGCACCGGCCGGAGGCAGGGGAGGCGUGGCCACCUGUGGCUCGAACUCUCCCCAUCCACUCUACGGCACCACCUCGGACUCCCCGCGUCCGCUCUGCAGCACCGCCUCGGACUCCCCGCGUCCGCUCUGCGGCACCGCCUCGGACUCCCCCCGUCUGCUCUAUGGCACCGCCGGAAUGUGAACGCUGUUGCCCUGGACGUUUUCUCUCUCUGCUCAGUGCCCAGGCUCUUGGGUACACAGGCGGCCCCGGGUUUUAUUUGGAAAGGGUACAGAGAACAGUGAAGUAACCCACGUGCCUAAGCUUUGAUUGACAUGAAGAAAUGUAGAAGCUGCUGAAAUCCUGGUCAUUUUAGAACAAAGUAUCUUAUUAACAUUUUUCUAAAAGAAAGAAAUCAUUAAAAAAUUGAUCCCGGUUGAGGUAGAAGGAUCUCGUCCUCAUCCUCCUCAGUUCCUUCCAGAAUCAGCUUCGAGUUCAGCUGCAGAACGGGUUCUGGUGGUGGCUGGAGCAGCCCAGGAGGGUGCCGUUGCGUCUGAGUUCACACCGGUGCCUGUGUGGUCUCCAGUUACGGUGCUGGCCGUGGAGUCUGGGUUCACACCGGUGCCCGCAUGGUCUCCAGUUACGGUGCUGGCCGUGGAGUCUGGGUUCACACCGGUGCCCGCGUGGUCUCCAGUUACGGUGCUGGCCGUGGAGUCUGGGUUCACACCGGUGCCCGCGUGGUCUCCAGUUACGGUGCUGGCCGUCGGGUCUGGGUUCACACCGGUGCCCGCGUGGUCUCCAGUUACGGUGCUGGCCGUGGAGUCUGGGUUCACACCGGUGCCCGCGUGGUCUCCAGUUACGGUGCUGGCCGUGGAGUCUGGGUUCACACCGGUGCCCGCGUGGUCUCCAGUUACGGUGCUGGCCGUCGGGUCUGAGUUCACACCGGUGCCCGCGUGGUCUCCAGUUACGGUGCUGGCCGUGGAGUCUGGGUUCACACCGGUGCCCGCGUGGUCUCCAGUUACGGUGCUGGCCGUGGAGUCUGGGUUCACACCGGUGCCCGCGUGGUCUCCAGUUACGGUGCUGGCCGUCGGGUCUGAGUUCACACCGGUGCCCGCAUGGUCUCCAGUUACGGUGCUGGCCGUGGAGUCUGGGUUCACACCGGUGCCCGCAUGGUCUCCAGUUACGGUGCUGGCUGUCGGGUCUGAGUUCACGCUGGUGCCCGCGUGGUUUCCAGUUACAGUGCUGGCCGCUUGUACCUUUCUGGGAAGUUAGAAGGAGGAUCAUUUCAUCGCCUCCCUGUCCUCCCACACCUUGACCUAUACUGGGCCACCGCGAAUUCUUCCUUUUAACUGUUUCUCUCUUCACAGGCAACACUGGCGUUUUGUGGUCCACGUUUGCCUCUUCUGAAAACGGAUUCUGUGUUGCUUUAUAGAAUCACAUGGUCUCUUUUAUGAAUUUCGCUUUUCUUUCAUAAAAUAAUCGUGCUUUUAUCUCUUCAAUCUCAACUCUGUUCCCUGGCACAGGCUCUUCCCAGCUCAAAAAUUAAAAGUAAUCUUUGAUUACGCUUAAUACUUUCUAAAGUUUUGAAGUUUAUCAGCAUGUGGGUUACAGAACAUUGACUAUUUAUUUAAUGGAAAAUUACAUUCUAAGUAGAGUAUUAAAGUGAAAGGGAUCUUUUGAUUUUAUUAAAAUAUUCAGGUAAACAUAUGAAAAUGCCUUCGCCAAACUUCAUGCUUGUAUAUCAUGAAAACAUUAAGCUGCUAAGCUCUCUCUGCUCCCGGGAAUGCAUUAUUAGAGUAUGUGUUUGAAGGUGUCAUUCCAGUCUUAGUUUUAGGUAUUUUUUAAAGGGGUUGGCUGGAGAAGUGACAUUUAGCAUUGAGUGAAUGUUUGAUAAAGAUUUGUCUCUAUAUAAAAAUAUUUAAAAACAAUCUUUAGCGUUUCCUUUCAGGGUUCACCCAUUAAAGAAUGGUCUUGUAAAAAAAAAACAUGUUAAGAGUGUUGGCGCCCAGAGGUGCUACCCUGCCCACAGUUUCAUCAUCCGCUGUCGCCAGGUGACACGUCCAGUGUUUAGCUGCAUGUCAGACGUGGCCACAGGGCCACAGGACAUCCCUGCGGACGGAUGUUCUUAUGCAGAUUAAUUAGGAUGGAGACUGCUGCAGAACUGUAAACCCCCCAGGGGCUGACGGAAGCCUGGGAACACCCGAGACACCAGAAUCCGCUGCUACAGUGGGUGGAAGGAAACCUCCCUGGAAGAUGGGACAUGUAAUAAGGAGAAAGUACCAAGGCACGUGGUGCUUUGAAAACUGAGAUGUUUUAAUUAAAUUAACAAUUAAAAUAAUUUAAUUAUGUGAAUUAUUUGAACUCAUUUUAGUUCUUUUUAGGAAAUUAAUACUUUAAGCAAGUUUGUUUUUGUGAAUCGUUUGAAUUAAUUGAGUCAGCACAAAUGUUAGCAUUGAUAUCUGACCCCCUUCCAGGGUUGGGGCAGAGGAGAUGGGGGCGGAGGAGCCAGGCCUCCAACCCGCUUUCCCCUGGAGCUCAGCCAGAAUUCCCCAUUGAGGAGCCCUCAGCUCCCUGAGAGCCAGGAGCUCUUGCGGAGAAGCCACUGUCUGCACGCCACCUGCUUCGAUGACCCUGCUCUGCCAUCCCUGUGCUCCAAGGGCCGGGCCCUGCCGUUGCCUGUGCCAGACGGGUCUCAGGGAGAUGCCGGCCAGCAGGUAUGCAUGGCGAGGCCUGGGCAUCAAGGCCCGGAUUCUAUGGCUGCCAGUUUCAUUCUCUCGUUGUUUGUCCCCCUAGCAAGACUUAUGAGGUUCCUUGAGGACAAGACUCCCUCCUGCCACCUGGUCUGUUUCCUGAACAUUCACUGCACUAGCACGGCCCCGGGACGCAGCCCUUGGGAAUCAGGCCGUCGGCCAUGGUAGAGCGGCUGGCACUGCUCGGCACCGUGACGGACGUUGGCCGCUGUGCUUCACUUUGGGGACAUGUUUAAGUACAAAACUAAUUUUAAAAUUUCACCAUUAUUUCAAGACAGCUGAGAGCAUAUUAGCACAGAAUCCCUGGUCUAAAUGAAAUCGAAGAGUUCUUAUUAAUUAUUCAUAAUGCCAUGAAUAUGUUACCUUAUUUUUUAUAAUUGCCAGUCUGUAUAAUUAACCUUUCAUUUGGUUAAAGUACUUAACAUUAAGUAGAGCUAUAAUUACAACUGUUUUUAAAAGUAUAUGGAAGAAUGUUUAAAUGUUUAAUUAGAACCACUUUUUUUAGCUUCAUAAAGAAUUUUUUUUACUUGUCAACAAGGAUCUUUAAUUAUUUAAACCAAAAGAGCAGAACAGACCAGAAAAGAAAAACAACUAGUCAAGCUGGGAACUGCAAUGGUGGCGUCGUUCCGUGAGUCUCGGGUUUUGCUUCUUGGGUUUGUGGUCAGAGUCCUUACCUUUGAUUUCCUAACACAGGUUGUUAGAGUUGGAAGUGAGUGUGGAGAUGAGUUAAUCCGACUUUAUUCUUUCACGGAUGAGAAAGCGAAUUAUCUUCAGCAAGGUGGGUGCAGGUGUGGCCCCCGGGGGACACUGUGGGGAAUAGGCCGCCCUCGUGGGGAGCCAAGUUCGUCGUCUCCGGGACAGAGCCCAGGACACUUCCACGGCUGGCUGGCCUCUUCCUAGAACCCCACACAUUGCAAAGGAUGGAGUCCAGAUCUAUACUGUAAAGAAAUGAGGGCAGUUACAGAAAGCACCACAUUCUCGGCUGAGUGGCUCUGGGCACCCCAACGUUGGGACACCUCAGCAUCAUGUAUGGCGAUCCUCAGGCUGUGCCCAGCAGUGAGGCUGGGCCUGAUCAAGGCUGCGGUCUCCACCCUGAGAGCGAGGGCUUCCUUCCCCCAGCGCGGGUUAAAGCAGUGAGGCCGGGCCUGAUUGAAGCUGCGGUCUCCACCCUGACAGCUUGAGCUUCCUUCCCCCAGUACGGGUUAAAGCAGUGAGGCUGGGCCUGCUGGAGGCUGUGGUCUCCACUCUGAGAGUGAGGGCUUCCUUCCCCCAGUGUGGGUUAAAGCACCAUGUGUCCACCUAUGCAGUGGCUGGUCCCAGUGUGCCCUGAGGGGCAGAAACCCUGGGUCCUGCCGCUGGUCUGGGGUAUCUACUUCCCAUUCCUGCAGUUCCUGGGAGUGUCUGUGUGUCCAGGGGGCUCCGAUCCCUGCCUCAGGACCACGGGUGAGGGGUCAAGAUCGCCCGCUUUGGAGUUGGCCCGGAUCUUGGUUCUGUGUGGCUCUGGAGCAGUUUUGUCCUCAGGAGAGGGAUCCUCACAGCCGCCUCUUGGGACCAUGAGGAGAAUUAAUAGGAUGACCCCCAGGUAGCUACCGUAGCCCUGUGCAGGGCCAACCGUGUGUCUCCACCGCCAGUUCCUUCCGUCUGUGCUCCCACCAACUGUCACAUCACCAGCCUUUAUUUUCUUUUUCUUAGACCCAGACAGCGAGUGCCCCACUGGCCUCGGCAGCCCCUUCUCUAACUUGUCCUCAAAUCAGUUCCUCACGGACAGCCCUGACCAGCCAUUGGCAUGACCAAAACCCCACCAAAUAGAACCCAACUUUCCUAUUAAGCUGUGCAGAGCAGUCCCAGCCCCACUUCCCACAGGCUGACCUCAUUCGCCAUGGGAUCCGUGGUUCUCACCUGGGGCUGGGGGUGCCCCUGGCAUCUGGUGGGGAGUGUCAGGGAUGCCCUUCCAGGUCCAGGAUAGUCCCCCAGCUGGUGGCCGACAGACAGCAGCACACAGCCUGAUGUCCCUGUGGCUUCCGGUUCCCCGAGGCCAGCUGUGCUUUGCUGCCUCUUCAUCUUCUCAGACGGGUGCCCUCUCUCCACCUUCGCUGGUUAGCAAUGUUCAUCCAUUAGAGCUCAAAGCACUGCCUGCUGGCAGCACAGCCCCUUCUCCUGGCCCUCCGUCCGCCUGUGCCCCACGGUCUGUGCCGUGUCCCCGCCUUCCGCCUGUGCCGCAUGGUCUGUGCCAUGUCCCCGCAGGCCCAUCAGAGCGAGGCUCCCAGGGACAGAGCGUUUCCUGUUUGUGUCUCUGUCCCACCCUCUCUGGACCUGGCAUGAUGCCCGUUGCCAACAGAGGUCUUGGGUUGAUUGUCACCAAAGCAGAUAAUCUAUAUGGCUGUAAAUGGCUGUAAACAUGCUUGAUUGGGGUAUUUUUUAAGUAAUUGGAUAUGUAAACAUUUGAAUGUGACACAGGUGGAUUUUUGGGCCAAUGGUCUCGUUCUUCAGGGAAUAACCACAGGCCCAUCCACAAGGACCAUUUCUGGCUGAUUUAUGGAACACUGUUCUACCUGGUUAAUUUUGGACGUUAUCUCAGCCUGAGAGGUAGGUCAGCAAUGUGACGAAGAGCACUGGUUUGAAUCCUAAUCUGCUACUUAGAAGCUGCAUAUUUUCCUGCCACGUUCUGUGCCUCAGUUUCUUGCUUGGUUAGGUAGGAAAGGUAUGAGCUACCUCAGAGUGGUGAGUGAGGCCUGCAUCGAGUGUCCGCAUUAAAGUGCCGAAAACUGGACCCAGAGUGUUGAUAUUUAAAGACCUUUAAACAUUCCGAUGCUGCAUUUUAGUACCCCGGUAAAACAGCAAAGUCGUUACAGAUGCAGACACAGACCCUGGGUGAGGUGGGGGACUGAUGGUGGGAGGUGGGUCACCAACCCCGUAAUGAGGGCGUGGUCUGUUCGAGGCUGAAUGAAGUGCACGUCUUCACGUGUACCACGGUGGUGCCUCUCGUGAAGUCCUGUAAGCGUCCACGUGGCUGAGCCGUGCGGUCUGUUUGUGACGUCUGGCAGGAGCAGAGCUUUUGGGCGCAGCCUCGCUCUUGCGUGCACGGCCCUCAACGAUCUCAAAAGUCUGAGGCUUAAAGCAGGCUUGGGGUUUCCCUUACACCUCCCGGACAUCUAAUUUGCCUGGCAAACAUGUUAUUCUUGGGUGUAAAGGUGAAGGAGUGGGUGACUCUGGUGAAAGUGUACUAAUUACUGCACUUCUGGGUCAGUGGCGCUCGGUUGAAGACACUGUCUGCCCUGGGUGGACAUCUCUGGUGUGGUGAGAACCGGCGGCUGGAUGUCGCGAGGUUGCCAAGAAGAUGCCCGCUUUUUCCUUUUUCCUCAGUAACAAAACCCUACUUUGUUUAGGGAAGCAGCGAACCCAGCUGAAAAUCCAGUUCUCUUGUACGGCAGAGCGGCUGGUGACACAGGUCCAGAUGCUGGGAUGCUGAUGGGGGGUUUUGGAGAGGGAGGUGUCGGGAGGGUUUCCCGACCCACAGCAGCCCUGGGCCCUUGUCCGGCCUUCUUGCCCGGGGCAUGACGCCUGGAGGGAAAGCAGCUUCGGGGGCCUGAGGGCCACAAGGCAGAGUCCUGGUGUGUGGGGCAGGCCUGGGCCAGGCUCCUUGGAGGAUGUUACAGAGCCACUGCGUGUGCGGGGACCACCCAUCUCUGAGCCCCACGCGGAUUUUCCUCCAUAGCCGAGCGAAAUCCUGGUACGGCGAGCGAGGCAGUCAGAGGCACCUUUUGUGGAAGGAGGACAAAGCUGGAGGGAAGGAGGUUUUCCUAAAAGGCACAAGGCACUGAUACUGCGUUAGGAGUAAUUCCUAGGAGCGUGGUAGCUGGUGGGUGGAAAACUGUAGCCAAAGAAUAAAUGGGAAUGGCCCUUCUUGGUAUUUAACUGAUUCGUUCACGAAUGGUCCAAACAGUUGUAGUGAAAAAAACAUUUUGGACACCGAUGUUUUCAUCCUGCCUGACGAUCGGCGUGACCGUGGGGUGUUCCAUCCUUCCUGGGCAACAGUGAGAGGGCCUGACAAUCGGCGUGACCGUGGGGUGUUCCAUCCUUCCUGGGCAACAGUGAGAGGGGCUCAGGCCCUUCUGGCCCCAUGCAGGCAUUUCCCCAGGGUGUGUCCCCCGUCCUGAAUAGGCCGGAAUGCCUCUGGGUGCAGCUGAGCCUCUUGAAAAGGGAAGAGUCAUGUGACAUGCUCUCGGUGAACAGGAAAAUGAGGGAGGACAAGGAGAGGGGCCUGGAGGUGAGGAGGAUGGUGACCAACACCAGGGAUGGGAUGGAGGGUAACCCCGGGGACGGGGGACGGAGGGUAACUCCGGGGACGGGGGGACGGAGGGUAACACCGAGGAUGGGGGAUGGAGGGUAACACCACUUCUCCAGGUGCCUUUGGGGGAUGCUGCCGCCCCUCCCACCCCAGAGUGAAGUCAACAGGAUUCUGUCCCCAGGAGCCCCAGAGCCUGGCAGCUGGGAUUGGCCCAGUAUGAACCACUGUUCACUGGCUCUGCACCCUGGGACAGGCUCCCUGGUGUUUCCGCCCCAGUUUCCCAUCUGGACAGUGAGACCCUGACUGUCCCCGUCACAGGUGCACAUGGAGGCCUGGACUCUAGCAUGUCAUCGGCACUCGUUAGUGUCAGCCCUCGUUAGCGUUUCUUUUGUCGUGGUCCAUGGACGAAGUGGAUCUUGCUUUGUGUGUUCACAGACCUCCUGCUCACUUUACCUUCUGGGAACACUUUGUAAAUAGCUUCGUAUGUGGGGAGGACUCAAGUGAUUAAUUGAAUAUUUCAUCAGGUGCAGUUCUCUGUGUCCCAGCUUGCAAAACGCUCUUUUGACACAACAUUUGGUGAAAUUUCCAGGGACUCCUGUGGUCAGCCUCAUGGUUUCACUCUGUCACUUUCUAAUGCAGUGUUCUUUGGGAGUCUUUUAAAUUAGGUGCCCUCAUUUAAAAGUAAGUUUUAUAAUAUGCAGUUUCAGGUUACUUCUUUACCUUUGUGUCUUAGGCAGUGGCUCCCCACCUGUGAGUAGUCAGAAAGGUUCACGCAGUUUUCCAGGGCGGCCUUUGCAUUUACUGGAACUAUUAAGAGCUCGUUCCUGCUUCAGCCGUGAUUGAAGCGCAGUGUGCGUGAGGCCGUGCAUGGCUUAGCAUCUUCUGCAGGCUAGAGGUCACUUUCUGUCCUUCCCCGAGCCUGCUCUGCUGUGCUGAGUGUUCCCUGUGGGCGACGGUCACGCUGUCUGGCACAGGCCACCGAGGCCACAGGGCAGGCUCCCCGUAGGGGAGCCUGCAGAAAGGCAGAGCCCGGCCUCUUCGCGGCCUUUCACAGGGAGCAGAAAGCGUAAGCCUGUUAUUAGAGCUGUGCUAGCCCAGAAAGCCUCCGAACAGUGUUUAAUUUAGGAAUCGGCUCCUACCAACUGCCCAUUUUUAGGAUGUAUUUGAGUUUUUGUGAUUUUUUUUCUGCACUGAAGCUACUGUGCUGGCUCUGAGUCACUGUCAUGGGACUUCACGUUGCCCUGACGGGAAGCGGCGGGGGAGGAGGGCUGCGCAGAGGCUUGCGGCCGUGAUAAUGAAGGGCUUGUUGCCUCUUGGGACAGUGAGUUCAAGCUGUU